GGCUCCCUCCCGGUCCCCACCUCGGCCCCGGGCUCCGAAGCGGCUCGGGGGCGCCCUUUCGGUCAACAUCGUAGUCCACCCCCUCCCCAUCCCCAGCCCCCGGGGAUUCAGGCUCGCCAGCGCCCAGCCAGGGAGCCGGCCGGGAAGCGCGAUGGGGGCCCCAGCCGCCUCGCUCCUGCUCCUGCUCCUGCUGUUCGCCUGCUGCUGGGCGCCCGGCGGGGCCAACCUCUCCCAGGACGGCUACUGGCAGGAGCAGGAUUUGGAGCUGGGAACUCUGGCUCCACUCGACGAGGCCAUCAGCUCCACAGUCUGGAGCAGCCCUGACAUGCUGGCCAGUCAAGGGCCUCUGCUCUGCUGGGAGCACCCAUUGGCUAUUUCUUGGAAAUGGAAUUCCAGUAACCAAGAAAGGAAUAAGCAGACAGGCAGGGGUAAGGUGGUGGCAGGAAGGCCAAACGUAGAACAACAGAUAUGUCUGUGUGUUUUCAGAGACAGCCAGCCCUGGACAUCUGAUGAAACAGUGGUGGCUGGUGGCACCGUGGUGCUCAAGUGCCAAGUGAAAGAUCACGAGGACUCAUCCCUGCAAUGGUCUAACCCUGCUCAGCAGACUCUCUACUUUGGGGAGAAGAGAGCCCUUCGAGAUAAUCGAAUUCAGCUGGUUACCUCUACGCCCCACGAGCUCAGCAUCAGCAUCAGCAAUGUGGCCCUGGCAGACGAGGGCGAGUACACCUGCUCAAUCUUCACUAUGCCUGUGCGAACUGCCAAGUCCCUCGUCACUGUGCUAGGAAUUCCACAGAAGCCCAUCAUCACUGGUUAUAAAUCUUCAUUACGGGAAAAAGACACAGCCACCCUAAACUGUCAGUCUUCUGGGAGCAAGCCUGCAGCCCGGCUCACCUGGAGAAAGGGUGACCAAGAACUCCACGGAGAACCAACCCGCAUACAGGAAGAUCCCAAUGGUAAAACCUUCACUGUCAGCAGCUCGGUGACAUUCCAGGUUACCCGGGAGGAUGAUGGGGCGAGCAUCGUGUGCUCUGUGAACCAUGAAUCUCUAAAGGGAGCUGACAGAUCCACCUCUCAACGCAUUGAAGUUUUAUACACACCAACUGCGAUGAUUAGGCCAGACCCUCCCCAUCCUCGUGAGGGCCAGAAGCUGUUGCUACACUGUGAGGGUCGCGGCAAUCCAGUCCCCCAGCAGUACCUAUGGGAGAAGGAGGGCAGUGUGCCACCCCUGAAGAUGACCCAGGAGAGUGCCCUGAUCUUCCCUUUCCUCAACAAGAGUGACAGUGGCACCUACGGCUGCACAGCCACCAGCAACAUGGGCAGCUACAAGGCCUACUACACCCUCAAUGUUAAUGACCCCAGUCCGGUGCCCUCCUCCUCCAGCACCUACCACGCCAUCAUCGGUGGGAUCGUGGCUUUCAUUGUCUUCCUGCUGCUCAUCAUGCUCAUCUUCCUUGGCCACUACUUGAUCCGGCACAAAGGAACCUACCUGACACAUGAGGCAAAAGGCUCCGACGAUGCUCCAGACGCGGACACGGCCAUCAUCAAUGCAGAAGGCGGGCAGUCAGGAGGGGACGACAAGAAGGAAUAUUUCAUCUAGAGGCGCCUGCCCACUUCCUGCGCCCCCCAGGGGCCCUGUGGGGACUGCUGGGGCCGUCACCAACCCGGACUUGUACAGAGCAACCGCAGGGCCGCCCCUCCCGCUUGCUCCCCAGCCCACCCACCCCCCUGUACAGAAUGUCUGCUUUGGGUGCGGUUUUGUACUCGGUUUGGAAUGGGGAGGGAGGAGGGCGGGGGGAGGGGAGGGUUGCCCUCAGCCCUUUCCGUGGCUUCUCUGCAUUUGGGUUAUUAUUAUUUUUGUAACAAUCCCAAAUCAAAUCUGUCUCCAGGCUGGAGAGGCAGGAGCCCUGGGGUGAGAAAAGCAAAAAACAAACAAAAAACAAAACCCUGGAGUGUUAGGAGGAGAGUGAAGGUAGAGGGGUGAGGAAGGGUAAGGGGCAGGGCUGGUUUCAGCUGGGGGCUCUCACCAGCCCUCCUUUCAGCCUCUACAACAGAGCAGCUUCCCAGACUUCUCCAGGAACCCAGAAACGGGAUGGUUGUCGGCAAAGGUUGGGAGUGGCUUUUCCUCUGGUAGCCACACACCUGAGCACUACGGACAGGGAGGCAGGUGCCACCUUGACACCUCUCUUCCAUAGCAAUGGGAAAGUGAUGAGUGCGGGAGUCCUGAGGAGAUGUGGCCUGCAGACAACAUGCAGCCAUGCAGGGACCCAGGACUGUAACCUGGGGAGGACGCGGGUCCCUGCAAGGAAGAGUAGAUUUGGAGAGGAAGGAUGGAGGUGGACUCUCACCCCAUUCCCCCCGGAAAUGAACAAAGCCGGGCCCUUUCCAUAGGAACUGCCCUUGGAGAUAGCAGAGUGUGGCUGCCCCUCCUUGCUCCAGCAGCAGUGGGAGAGGCACUGCUCUGGGGCCUGAACUGCCUCUGCUUCCCCCCCUGAGGGGCCCCUCACUCUUACCCAAGACUCUGGAUUGUUGCACGGCAACCACUCCUCCCAUGGCAUUGCUCAGCAACUACUUCUCCCUUCCCGGCCACCCUGUGCCCCCUUCCUGGUCCCAACGCCAGCCCUUCAUCCUUCCUCCCUCAGCAGCCAGGCAGACAUAACAACAAAACUACUAAAAGGAGCUUCACUGCAGUGAGCUGUUUCCUGCCCAAACUAAGGGAAUAAUGUGAACUGUGUGCAUGUGUGUGGUGUGUAUGCAUGUGUGCAUGUGUGUGUGUGUGUGUGCAUGUGUGUGAGUGAGUGAGAGGCAGAGCGAGGAACUGAGGAGGAGGGCUAAGAGCCAGGGGUCCUGGGCAAGUGGACAGGGCUGUGGGACAUGUUGGGGAGGCUUUGGGAAUGGGGUAUUCCUAGUCAGGGUUCACACCUCACCUGGGAUGUUGUUCCAUGCUGGUAUUUCCUCUGCCACCCCCAAUGCCCAUCGGUCUUGGAGAAAGGAGUCCCCGGGUGUGUGUUUGCCCAGCUGUCCAUUCUAUCUCUCCCUUAAACACAGAGCAUUCAGCCCUUCCCUGGAUUUCCCUCCUCUGAGCCAUGGAGUCAGUGCCACAGCCUUUGCUAUGCACCUCUCAGGCCUCUCCUUGGCGUUGACCCUGGAAAGACCUACCACCACCUAUUUUUUCCCAUAGUCUGUACCCAGUGAGUUGAAGGCUGGGUCCCCACCCUUCCUUUUGAUUUCCUGUCUUCCUUCUCGUGGCCCCAGCUGGUUGCUGUGGAGAUGAGGUUCCUGGUCCUCCCUGUCCUGGCUGGACUGCCCCGCCUCAGAUCCAGGAUGCCCUUGGCAUCGCUCCCACCCUCCCCCAGCUUUUCCUCCCUGGUCUGACAAUGGGCAUGCAAAAAGGGGCAGCUGCAAUCUAGCAGGCCUGCCCACCCCCUUCAGUUCAGGUAAUACAGUUGUGAAUCUUCCAGCCGCUGGUUAGGGCCUUGGGCACCACAGGCAGCCCCUCACCUAAGCCGGGGCCUACUCCUCUUACAACAGCAAGAGAGCCCUGGGGCCCCAGGCCUGUUGAGCUUCUUGUCUCCCAGCACCCGCUUUUGGGAAAAUGACUUUUCCUCUUCAAGCUGAACCACUCUGUCCAUAUUACACAGAAGCCAUAUUUGUACGGGGGGGUGGGAGGGAGAGGGGCUGUUGUGCUGUGUGUGUCUGUCCAGGGGUGGGGGGGUGGGGGAAGGGAGCAGGGAGGGGACCGUGUAUCUUUAUAAUCUUUCUAACUCUCCUGUGCUAAUCUCAGAGGGGUCACCCUCAAUAUAUCUGGAUUAUCCGUGUCAUUCAGCUGCCUCCUUUCUGGUCCUCUUGCUGCUGCUGGGAUGUGUGUAUGUGAGGGUCUUCUUCCCAUACCCCUUGCACCUGGUGCCUGGUGCCUCAAAAGGUGGUGUGUCCCUUGCCAGGCCACUCUCAAGAAUAUCUAUGUACAGCAACAAUAUAACUCUACAAGGGA